AUCGCUCAGGCGGCUUGUCGUUAUUUUUUCUUUCUUUCGCCAAUUAUAUUUGUUUGGGGAAAAGCAAACAAAAAAAACAAAAAAACACUUGCCCUAUUGCCGGCCUUGGGGAUCUGGUGGCCACAUCGAGAGCUUUUGAAGUCCCUUCUUUUAAUCGCCUUUAUUGGUGCUAGAUUAAAACAUUACUAUCCCAUGUUGUGCAGCUGGGGAGAAAGGGAAAUUGAAAGAGGAAGACUUGGUGUAGGGAUGCUGUUUGGAAUAUUCUCUCAUAUUCUUUACUGGCAUCAUAUUAAUCGGUUGAUGGAUUCGGCUAGGGACACUGAAUUGCACUCCUGUAUGGAUCUGUGGAUAUCUAUAUAUAAUACAAAUAAUACUGAAUAUUAUUGGGCCUAAAAUAACCAAUUAAGUGAUUCAUACAAGGAAAAACUUAGAUAUAAAAAGAAACUGCGCCCUCUGCUGUUAAUUUUAGUACCCUCACCCGGGGACUUUUUUUUUUUUUCCUUCAGAAAUCCACUUAAGAGUAGGCUGUCAUCUUACAGGGCAAGGGAAGAAAAUUCCUAGCGGGGAUUUUAAAGCAACUUUACUUGGAAAAGUCGCAGGUUGAGCUCCUAUAGUUGCAUCAGGGUGUUGGUGCCAGAAGAAAAGAAUGAUUGAUGGGAAACAGACACCGGGCUAUAGACACUCAUCCUUUUGCUUCAGAUACUGAUAUCUCAGCCUGCUUGAGCAUCCCUUGUGAGCUGUGAACAUUGAGGAUCACUCAGGGUUAUCGGAUGUACAACGGGAGAGCCAUCGCUUUGCUAAAUUAUUAUCUGCAAUUGGACAUCUUUUACAAAAACCAAACUAGACCUGAGUCUAAUAGAUAUGUUCUAAGACAAAGAAAAAGCUGCAAGUUGUUAACGCCUAACACACAAGUAUGUUAGGCUUCCACCAAAGUCCUCAAUAUACCUGAAUACGCACAAUAUCUUAACUCUUCAUAUUUGGUUUUGGGAUCUGCUUUGAGGUCCCAUCUUCAUUUAAAAAAAAAUACAGAGACCUACCUACCCGUACGCAUACAUACAUAUGUGUAUAUAUAUGUAAACUAGACAAAGAUCGCAGAUCAUAAAGCAAGCUCUGCUUUAGUUUCCAAGAAGAUUACAAAGAAUUUAGAGAUGUAUUUGUCAAGAUUCCUGUCGAUUCAUGCCCUUUGGGUUACGGUGUCCUCAGUGAUGCAGCCCUACCCUUUGGUUUGGGGACAUUAUGAUUUGUGUAAGACUCAGAUUUACACGGAAGAAGGGAAAGUUUGGGAUUACAUGGCCUGCCAGCCGGAAUCCACGGACAUGACAAAAUAUCUGAAAGUGAAACUCGAUCCUCCGGAUAUUACCUGUGGAGACCCUCCUGAGACGUUCUGUGCAAUGGGCAAUCCCUACAUGUGCAAUAAUGAGUGUGAUGCGAGUACCCCUGAGCUGGCACACCCCCCUGAGCUGAUGUUUGAUUUUGAAGGAAGACAUCCCUCCACAUUUUGGCAGUCUGCCACUUGGAAGGAGUAUCCCAAGCCUCUCCAGGUUAACAUCACUCUGUCUUGGAGCAAAACCAUUGAGCUAACAGACAACAUAGUUAUUACCUUUGAAUCUGGGCGUCCAGACCAAAUGAUCCUGGAGAAGUCUCUCGAUUAUGGACGAACAUGGCAGCCCUAUCAGUAUUAUGCCACAGACUGCUUAGAUGCUUUUCACAUGGAUCCUAAAUCCGUGAAGGAUUUAUCACAGCAUACGGUCUUAGAAAUCAUUUGCACAGAAGAGUACUCAACAGGGUAUACAACAAAUAGCAAAAUAAUCCACUUUGAAAUCAAAGACAGGUUCGCGUUUUUUGCUGGACCUCGCCUACGCAAUAUGGCUUCCCUCUACGGACAGCUGGAUACAACCAAGAAACUCAGAGAUUUCUUUACAGUCACAGACCUGAGGAUAAGGCUGUUAAGACCAGCCGUUGGGGAAAUAUUUGUAGAUGAGCUACACUUGGCACGCUACUUUUACGCGAUCUCAGACAUAAAGGUGCGAGGAAGGUGCAAGUGUAAUCUCCAUGCCACUGUAUGUGUGUAUGACAACAGCAAAUUGACAUGCGAAUGUGAGCACAACACUACAGGUCCAGACUGUGGGAAAUGCAAGAAGAAUUAUCAGGGCCGACCUUGGAGUCCAGGCUCCUAUCUCCCCAUCCCCAAAGGCACUGCAAAUACCUGUAUCCCCAGUAUUUCCAGUAUUGGUAAUUGUGAAUGCUUCGGCCACUCCAAUCGAUGCAGUUAUAUCGAUCUGCUAAAUACAGUCAUUUGCGUGAGCUGUAAACACAACACUAGAGGGCAGCACUGUGAGUUAUGCAGGCUGGGCUACUUCAGAAAUGCUUCUGCACAACUGGACGAUGAGAAUGUGUGCAUAGAGUGUUAUUGUAACCCUUUGGGCUCAAUCCAUGAUCGUUGUAAUGGCUCAGGAUUUUGUGAGUGUAAGACUGGAACAACAGGGCCUAAGUGUGAUGAGUGUCUGCCGGGAAAUUCCUGGCACUACGGCUGUCAACCGAAUGUCUGCGACAACGAGCUCCUGCACUGCCAGAACGGAGGGACGUGCCACAACAACGUGCGCUGCCUGUGCCCGGCCGCAUACACGGGCAUCCUCUGCGAGAAGCUGCGGUGCGAGGAGGCUGGCAGCUGCGGCUCCGACUCUGGCCAGGGCGCGCCCCCGCACGGCUCCCCAGCGCUGCUGCUGCUGACCACGCUGCUGGGAACCGCCAGCCCCCUGGUGUUCUAGGUGUCACCUCCAGCCACACCGGACGGGCCUGUGCCGUGGGGAAGCAGACACAACCCAAACAUUUGCUACUAACAUAGGAAACACACACAUACAGACACCCCCACUCAGACAGUGUACAAACUAAGAAGGCCUAACUGAACUAAGCCAUAUUUAUCACCCGUGGACAGCACAUCCGAGUCAAGACUGUUAAUUUCUGACUCCAGAGGAGUUGGCAGCUGUUGAUAUUAUCACUGCAAAUCACAUUGCCAGCUGCAGAGCAUAUUGUGGAUUGGAAAGGCUGCGACAGCCCCCCAAACAGGAAAGACAAAAAACAAACAAAUCAACCGACCUAAAAACAUUGGCUACUCUAGCGUGGUGCGCCCUAGUACGACUCCGCCCAGUGUGUGGACCAACCAAAUAGCAUUCUUUGCUGUCAGGUGCAUUGUGGGCAUAAGGAAAUCUGUUACAAGCUGCCAUAUUGGCCUGCUUCCGUCCCUGAAUCCCUUCCAACCUGUGCUUUAGUGAACGUUGCUCUGUAACCCUUGUUGGUUGAAAGAUUUCUUUGUCUGAUGUUAGUGAUGCACAUGUGUAACAGCCCCCUCUAAAAGCGCAAGCCAGUCAUACCCCUGUAUAUCUUAGCAGCACUGAGUCCAGUGCGAGCACACACCCACUAUACAAGAGUGGCUAUAGGAAAAAAGAAAGUGUAUCUAUCCUUUUGUAUUCAAAUGAAGUUAUUUUUCUUGAACUACUGUAAUAUGUAGAUUUUUUGUAUUAUUGCCAAUUUGUGUUACCAGACAAUCUGUUAAUGUAUCUAAUUCGAAUCAGCAAAGACUGACAUUUUAUUUUGUCCUCUUUCGUUCUGUUUUGUUUCACUGUGCAGAGAUUUCUCUGUAAGGGCAACGAACGUGCUGGCAUCAAAGAAUAUCAGUUUACAUAUAUAACAAGUGUAAUAAGAUUCCACCAAAGGACAUUCUAAAUGUUUUCUUGUUGCUUUAACACUGGAAGAUUUAAAGAAUAAAAACUCCUGCAUAAACGAUUUCAGGAAUUUGUAUUGCAAUUUCUUAAGAUGAAAGGAACAGCCACCAAGCAGUUUCACACUCACUUUACUGAUUUCUGUGUGGACUGAGUACAUUCAGCUGACGAAUUUAGUUCCCAGGAAGAUGGAUUGAUGUUCACUAGCUUGGACAACUUCUGCAAAAUAUGAGACUAUUUCCACUUGGGAAAAAUUACAACAGCAAAAAAAAAAAAAAAAAAAAAAAAAAAUCUAAGUGAUUGCCAAGAUUAUGCCAAAGCCUGUUGGCAGAGUACUAAGAGACUUUUAUUUUUAAGUCAUGCUAUUUUCACAGAUUGAUGGUGAUCAUGUGACUCUAGGGAUGCUGAUCUAUGUAUCUUUCCAAAUACAGUGUUUACAUGGAGUAUCACAAGACGCAACCUGGGGAACCAGGAAGGGAGCAGGGAAAUUGAGUGAUUUGCAAUUUGACUUUGAAUAUAUUCAGACUUAAGUAUUUAGAGGAAAUAUCAAAAUAUAAAGCAGCAAGUAGACAUAACUGCUGUUCCUGAGAAUAAAGUUUGUUUUAAGUGCUGCCCAAGGUGUAAUAAAUUCUUGUUUCUGCCUUUUAUUAGGCCAAUUACUGUGCAAGACAGCAAGGGGAGGCAGGUGGGGAAGAACCUUUGCAAAGUUUCAAAGAGGCUAAGACAGUGUGCAUUUCGUUCCCAGCACACUGUUGUCCUACAGAUUACAAGUGUAUUAGCAGCAGCAUCUCCUGGAAUCAAAAACAAUUAUCAGCCCGAACCAGAGUCUUAAGGACAAUGAAAUUCUACAUGACUUGGUAGAACAAUAACCUAUGAUAGUGUAAGGUCAGAAACCUAGUUCCAGUCUGAAUUCUUCACCCUGCUGCCACUCCUUGCUGAAACAGGGAAGGGGGGAGGAAUGUCUCCUGAUAAAUAACCUGGGUAAAAACUAGAUGAAGGAACAGCAUGUCUUAUUGGUUUUGUUCCCAGAAAAGCCAAUUCGAAGAAGGCAAUAAAAGGUAAACAGGUAAUGCCUGUGCUGCCUGCCACCCCACGUCUAAGUCUAUUGAAUGUUUGUUAUUCAAACCAACAGUCUCUUUUGAUGUAAGAAAUAAGGAAAGAUGGAAAUAAAUUAGAGCUUAGGCUUAGUGCCAGAGUGGCCAACCAGAAAUUGGAGAUUUACGUUGGAAGCAUAAAUAGAAAAUUAUAUUUCAGGCUCACCAAAGAAACACAUGAAAAUGCUGAUAACAUAGGGAGUUUGAGAUUAUUUAUAAUGAGGUGGAUUUCUGAUAUUAAAAUUAGAGUUUAAGUUGUCUUAUAGUUUAUUAGCACAAACCAAAGGCAGCCCAUGUUAUUUCUGGCAAAGAUGCACUUUAUCGUUAUCUGCUCAUGGCUUUGUCGCAACGCUCAGGAAUCAGACACUGCACACUUCAAUAGUUGGGAUUCCAAAAGCUAAUUCUAAAAUUUAAUGAAGGCCUGAUUUAAACUGAUUCAUCUGCAUUUUAUCUUUAUGAGGCCAUAAGAAUCUAAAUUGAUGAGGAAUAUCUUUCAUUCCGUGUAUUUAGAUAUAGUUUUCUGAAUUUCCUGAAGCGAUGUGAUCUGCUUUUAAUAAAAAUUCACUUUUAGGUGUACAACAAAUGGAAAUGAAAUGUUCUUUUUAAAUCUGGAUUCUCAAGUUCUUCUAAAGGAGCUACUCCUCUGAGGAAACCUCAACUCAGUGGACUUGAUUCAUCUGUUACUUUCCAGCAUUCUUACAAAGCUGGUUUCAUCUACAAUGUUGUGCCCUAAGAACAGGACUGGGGUGAAAAGCGGGUACUCAGUUGUUCAUAUAUUUGAGGUCCUAAUUCUUGGUAUUUUUUCCCUUUGAUAAAUCCCUUAAAGUGGCUUAAUGUAGUCUUGCAUAUGAGUUAAUCUAUCAACUUUCCCACAUAGAACUGAUAUAAUUCCUUCUAUCAAUAAUAUUGAUGGGCAUAACAUUUCAAAAAAUGGGACAAAGGUUCAGCUAUCUAGAAAGAUUUGCUAUUUAUAGGAAGAUAAUGGACAUGCCCUGCUGUGAUUUGAGGGUUAUUUAUUUCUGACCCUGUACACAGCCUAGGGGAAGAAUUUAGUCCAGCAAAGAGGGGACCUUGCUUAGAGAGACCCAUUCUGACUCUCCUCCAGCUUUCUCCCAGAUAUCAGGAACCUAGAGUUUCCUACUCAGAUAACCGCCCCCCACACGCACACUUUUAGGCCAAAUGUAGGCCCCCUCUGGGGGUUUAAACUCCUGGAGGCAAGCAACAUCCUGAGUGCAUAUACCUGGGCACAGGGAGUGGCAAAGGGUGCAUCUGUGUGGAUGGAUUAGGCCCUGGGGCCUGGAGUGUUCACUGUGGAAUUUACACACAAGCAAGGAGAAGCCACUUGCCAUGAAAACAAGAGUCCAGGGCUGAAAAAUAAAGGGAUGAGGGGUAGGAAGGAGAUAGACAAGGGCUACCACGAGGCUGGGGGCCAGUACAGAACACUGAACAGUCUAAGAAUUCUAAAUCUAUACCUGGGCUUCCAAGGGUUAUGAAAGCAUCAUGUGUCAAAGUGGCAGGAUGGAAGAUAAUUUAACAGUUUGUUAGCUUUAUGUAUGACUUUUAAAUACUUAGACAUGUGGCAUGGGGUCCUCCAUUGGUACUUUUGCACAAGAUCCUGCAGACAUUUGGGGUCGAUCUGCCUGAGGUGCCCUUGAGUCAGAUCCCUAAGUUGGCACAAACUGCUAACCACAUAACACAAAGAAAGGUCCAGGUUGGAAGAAGGCGUCUGCUCCACAGUUCAGCUGGCCCUGUAGUUAAUGCUCCCCUCACCUUCUCUUGGACCUGUGGUCUGACUGGAGUAUAAGAAAUUUUGGAUGCACUGGGGGAACAACUGUGAGGAAAUCUUGACAUCGAAUAUUUUGUUCCAUCUCCUUCACCCUCUACCAUCAAUAAUCCAGUAUGAUUGGGAUGUAAAGACCCAGCAUUCUGAAAUGGGAUGCUCUGUACUAUAUGGGAAAUGGGUUGUUGUACUUUACCGGUUGUUAAACACUAAAUAAAAUACCUGUUUAACAGAUUCUCUGCUCACAGGAUUGACCAA